GUUCCCGGUUCCCGAGCCGGGCCCCGGAGGCCUUUAAAUGCUGCCCAGGGCCGACGCGGCACGGCCCUCGCCACUUUUCUUGGUCGGGCAGCGGCAGCGGCAGCGGCAGCAAGCAGCCCCGUCGGCCCGGGUCCGGGGCCGUUCUGGGCCGCGGCAAGCACCUUCGCCCUCCCAGCUCGCGCUGCCUCCCUCCCCUCCCCUCCUCCCAGGCUCUGCCUGCCAGGUCGGCGCCGGGCCCCGGGCGCGCGCGCGCGCGCCCCCUCGUGUGUGCGCGCGCCCGCCGCCAGCUCGGACCCGCGCCCCCGCCCCCGCCCCGCGCAGGACAGCCCCGGGAUCCCCGCCCGCGCGCCGCGUCCCACGUACCCCGCCGCGCCGGGCAAGAAGAUGGCGGGAUCAGUGGCCGACAGCGAUGCCGUGGUGAAACUAGAUGAUGGCCAUUUAAACAACUCUUUGAGCUCUCCAGUUCAAGCGGACGUGUACUUCCCACGACUGAUAGUUCCAUUUUGUGGGCACAUUAAAGGUGGCAUGAGACCAGGCAAGAAGGUGUUAGUGAUGGGCAUCGUAGACCUCAACCCAGAGAGCUUUGCAAUCAGCUUGACCUGUGGGGACUCAGAAGACCCUCCUGCCGAUGUGGCAAUCGAACUCAAAGCUGUGUUCACAGAUCGGCAGCUACUCAGAAAUUCUUGUAUAUCUGGGGAGAGGGGUGAAGAACAGUCAGCAAUCCCUUACUUUCCAUUCAUUCCAGACCAGCCAUUCAGGGUGGAAAUUCUUUGUGAGCACCCACGUUUCCGAGUGUUUGUGGAUGGACACCAACUUUUUGAUUUUUACCAUCGCAUUCAAACGUUAUCUGCAAUUGACACCAUAAAGAUAAAUGGAGACCUCCAGAUCACCAAGCUUGGCUGAUUUAAACCACCUCUAUUUCAAAUAGGAUCACGUGCCACAACUAUCUGACUGUUGGUCUGGAAGAAGUGUCCUAGCAAGAUCUGGAGACUUAAAAAGAAAACAAAAACAAAUGGCAAGUUUCACUUAAGGGUGGUUUGCCCUUAAGAAGAAAGCUGUUGGGACAAAGACACCGAGCCAUUAUACCCAGAAUAAAAUAAUACAUUUAUGCUGGAUUUUAUUCAGACCAAACUAAAAUGGAUUUGUGAUGAUUUGUGAUUUGGUAGCAAAUUAUUCAUCUUUUCAAAGCAAGGCAAUGCUUAGAAACAGAAGUGCUAAAGACACUUAAAAAGCCAACAACAACGGUACAGUGAAAUCAAUGCAUUUCUGCACUAAAGUGGAAUUGUGUAGCACAACCAAUAUUUUAGUCAGGGUAUUUACAUAGAAUGUAGGUUGUUCAAGGUUUGACUUUUUUUUUGUUUUUUGUUUUUGUUUUUGUUUUUGUUUUGCACAGCAUAAUGUUAAUUCAGAUUGUUGAAGCUUUCUUGUAGUUAUUUAUUUAUACUCAAUGUAUGUAUUAAAGAAUGAACAAUGUCUCAAGAACAGCAAGUUGUAAACUUUUGAAUGUAUAAAUAUCUUAGGUCCAAGGGGAGAAAAUUACAUAUUACAAUUAUGAAACAGGUGAAUUUCUGCUUUAAAGAAUUGAGAUUCUCCAUACCCCUAAACUUAGGAUCUCUUGAUAUAAACUGCUGUAAGUGCUUUUGGGAAACCUUUGCAAAACCAUUUUGAUAAAACUGCUUUCCAAGUUAUUGUUGGUUAUGUAAAAUUCUAUUUACAUUGCUUUUUCUCCUUACUGGGAAUUAGCACAUUAUUGGCUUCCUUAAGACUAAUUAUUUCUCUCUUGAUUUAUAUAAUAGCUCAUUAAGUUGUUAUUAAUCAAAAACACAAAGAGGUGAUUGCUUAGACAAUUUUUAAAGUGACUAUAGUAUAAACUUUUAAAAGAAUAAUAUGAAAAUGACUGUGGAAUGCAGUGUAAAGCAGAAGCAAACGGCCCUGAAUAACUUACUUGGAAGUAAUUUAUAUCAACUUAAGCUGUUAGCUCAUUGUAUAACUUUUCUUAUGUGACCCUCACCAAUAUCCCUAAGUAAUGCCUUUGGAAGCUUCAGAGUAGAAGAUGCUUCCUACUGUGUUGGCUCUGAGGAGAUAGUAGGAUUAGAUAGGAUCCAGAUUAGGAAAUGAUCCAGUUAGUUUAUCUGAAAGGUUAACUCCCAGGACUCCAGGUCUUUGAAUCCAGCCAGUAGAGUGAAUGCUUCCAAUUAAGCUGUAGGUGUUACCCUGCACUUACGGAACUGAUCAAACAGGUGACUCCAACAGGAGGUUGCAGUACUGUAAACGUCACCGCAAGGCAAGGGAUGCUUAAAGUCCUGGGUUCUGGACUUUAAAAGCUACAUUGGCCCUGGAGGGAGGGACCCUUGGCAUUGCUUUGAUCAGGUAGUGAGGGAAGACAGGGUUCUGGGGUGGGGGUGUAUUUAUAUAUAAUUUAGGUUUUGUUUGUACAGCAUACUGUGUCUUGUAAUGACACAUCCUUGUCCUGCUUUCCUUUUUUGAGUUUUUUUUUUUUUUUUACACAACAUGCAGAGGCACUGAAGUGACCAUGUCAUUUUCAAGUGUCAAGAAUGUAGACAGUGUUUCAGUACCAAAGUCUAAAAUAAACUAAAAUUAUGAAUUUUUUAUAGGUGAUACAUUUGGAUUCUUCUCAACUUUGAAACUGUUUAGCACAGUUCCAUUGUAUUAUAUAAGAAGACACUGUAUCCAACAAGACUGGCUGUACAUUGAAAAGCUUUAUGUACCAGCCAACUUAUUUAACCAUAUUCAGCCUGUUCCGUGGGGGCUGUUCUGUGGUUCCAGGUAUUUUCAAGCCUGUGAUUAACUUCUCAUGGCUUGUCACUUAAAAGUCCCUAAAUUUGAGAGACUUAAAGGGCACCUUGAAAUACAUUUGUGGAGUUUUGAUCCAACUUAUGGUGGAAGAGCCCCAUAGGAAGACUGUUUUGAGUGGCCAACCAUUCCCACCCACUGCAUAAUUCAGCAGAAACUAGAGGAGCAGGGCGUGUACUGAUUGGAAUUGACACGCUUAUUCUGUCUACCUAUCAGCUAACUCAUUAGCAGCCAAGCCCUUAGGCAGCUUAGUGUGAAAAUACAAUGUUAACUGUUUGUUUCUCUGUGAGGUUAGUGGGAACCGCUUGGAUAAGCCUAUUGGGAUUAAUCUAAAUGAUGUGAUGAUUUGAUUCAGGUAUAGCCCAAAUUAGUAAGGGGCUUUAGCUGUAAACUGAAAACAAUAUUCACACCCUCUCCUGGGCCUGUAAGGUCUAAGGUGAGAAUUUCAGGAUGGAAAAUGCAAUGUAAAGCUUCCACAGGAAAGUAUUCGGGUAUGUAAGGUGUUAUUUCUGACCAGAGCCCUAGUUCUGCAAUAACCAAAACCAAGGAGUAUAAAUAACAAUCAGGCUCUGGGGGAAUAGAAAGCAGGCUUUAGACAAUCUGUCCAUUUCUACAGUAAAAUUGGAGUGAGUGUGUAUAUCUACUUAAAACUUAAUAGAAGUGACUUCUACUUUUUGGGCUAUUCCAGAAGUAUUUUAAAAUUAUUAUUUAAAAUUUUGAAGCCCCAUUUCAAAUCUUGCCGACCUUAGUUCAAAGCCCCCUGAGAGAUCACUUUUAGAAUUGAGGAUUUGUUAAAAUGGCAAGUCAUUUCAUUUGUGUUAAAAAGAAAAUACCCAAAAGGAAGGAGGGAGCCCUGUUUGCCUUGAGAUAAACGGCCUUGGCAUUUUCUGGCAUUAAUGUAGAAAUAAUGUUCCUAUGAUGACAUAUUUUCAAAGAAACACUUUCUUAUUUACUGUGUGGUGUAAAAUGUUGCUAAAUGUGUUGUUACAUUAUGUCACUGCUGAAAGUAAUUUGCACUAUAAUAAAGGAAUUUUCUACAAAA